AGAUCAGUUUGUCACCACCCAGGCUCCCUUGCCUUUGGCUGGGUGCAACUUCCAUUUUAGGUGUUGGAUCUGAGGGGGAAAAAAAAGAGAGAGGGAGAGAGAGAGAAAGAAGAGCAGGAAAGAUCCCGAAAGGAGGAAGAGGUGGCGAAAAAUCAACUGCCCUGCUGGAUUUGUCUUUCUCAGCACCUUGGCGAAGCCUUGGGUUUCUUUCUUAAAGGACUGAUUUUUAGAACUCCACAUUUGAGGUGUGUGGCUUUUGAAGAAAAUGUAUGUACUGACGGGAAAAGGAGGAUAAGCAAGUCGAAUUUUUGUCUUACGCUCUCUCCUUCCUGCUUCCUCCUUGCUGUGGUGGCUGGGAUGCUUCUUCCAUGAUUUUUUGAAUCUAGACUGGGCUGUUCUCUGUGUUAAACCAAUCAGUUGCGACCUUCUCUUAACAGUGUGAAGUGAGGGGGUCUCUCUCCCUCCUUCUCCUUCCUCUGUGAUUCACCUUCCUUUUUACCCUGCCCUGCGGCGGCUCCGCCCCUUACCUUCAUGGACGACUCAGAGGUGGAGUCGACCGCCAGCAUCUUGGCCUCUGUGAAGGAACAAGAGGCCCAGUUUGAGAAGCUGACCCGGGCGCUGGAGGAGGAACGGCGCCACGUCUCGGCGCAGCUGGAACGCGUCCGGGUCUCACCACAAGAUGCCAACCCACUCAUGGCCAACGGCACACUCACCCGCCGGCAUCAGAACGGCCGGUUUGUGGGCGAUGCUGACCUUGAAAGACAGAAAUUUUCAGAUUUGAAACUCAACGGACCCCAGGAUCACAGUCACCUUCUAUAUAGCACCAUCCCCAGGAUGCAGGAGCCGGGGCAGAUUGUGGAGACCUACACGGAGGAGGAUCCUGAGGGAGCCAUGUCUGUAGUCUCUGUGGAGACCUCAGAUGAUGGGACCACUCGGCGCACAGAGACCACGGUCAAGAAAGUAGUGAAGACUGUGACAACACGGACAGUACAGCCAGUCGCUAUGGGACCAGACGGGUUGCCUGUGGAUGCUUCAUCAGUUUCUAACAACUAUAUCCAGACUUUGGGUCGUGAUUUCCGCAAGAAUGGCAAUGGGGGACCUGGUCCCUAUGUGGGGCAAGCUGGCACUGCUACCCUUCCUAGGAACUUCCACUACCCUCCUGAUGGUUAUAGUCGCCACUAUGAAGAUGGUUAUCCAGGUGGCAGUGAUAACUAUGGCAGUCUGUCCCGGGUGACCCGCAUUGAGGAGCGGUAUAGGCCCAGCAUGGAAGGCUACCGGGCACCUAGUAGACAGGAUGUGUAUGGGCCCCAACCCCAGGUUCGGGUAGGUGGGAGCAGCGUGGAUCUGCAUCGCUUUCAUCCAGAGCCUUAUGGGCUAGAGGAUGACCAGCGUAGUAUGGGCUAUGAUGACCUGGAUUAUGGUAUGAUGUCUGAUUAUGGCACUGCCCGUCGGACUGGGACACCCUCUGACCCUCGUCGGCGCCUCAGGAGCUAUGAAGACAUGAUUGGUGAGGAGGUGCCAUCGGAUCAAUACUACUGGGCUCCUUUGGCCCAGCAUGAGCGAGGAAGUUUAGCAAGCUUGGAUAGCCUGCGCAAAGGAGGGCCUCCACCUCCUAAUUGGAGACAGCCAGAGCUGCCAGAGGUGAUCGCCAUGCUUGGAUUCCGCUUGGAUGCUGUCAAGUCCAAUGCAGCUGCAUACCUGCAACACUUAUGCUACCGCAAUGACAAGGUGAAGACUGACGUGCGGAAGCUCAAGGGCAUCCCAGUACUGGUGGGAUUGUUAGACCAUCCCAAAAAGGAAGUGCACCUUGGAGCCUGUGGAGCUCUCAAGAAUAUCUCUUUUGGACGUGACCAGGAUAACAAGAUUGCCAUAAAAAACUGUGAUGGUGUGCCUGCCCUUGUGCGAUUGCUUCGAAAGGCUCGUGAUAUGGACCUUACUGAAGUUAUUACCGGAACCCUGUGGAAUCUUUCAUCCCAUGACUCAAUCAAAAUGGAGAUUGUGGACCAUGCACUGCAUGCCUUGACAGAUGAAGUGAUCAUUCCUCAUUCUGGUUGGGAGCGGGAACCUAAUGAAGACUGUAAGCCACGCCACAUUGAGUGGGAAUCGGUGCUCACCAACACAGCUGGCUGCCUUAGGAAUGUAAGCUCAGAGAGGAGUGAAGCUCGCCGGAAACUUCGGGAAUGUGAUGGUUUAGUUGAUGCCCUCAUUUUCAUUGUUCAGGCUGAGAUUGGGCAGAAGGAUUCAGACAGCAAGCUUGUAGAGAACUGUGUUUGCCUUCUUCGGAACUUAUCAUAUCAAGUUCACCGGGAGAUCCCACAGGCAGAGCGUUACCAAGAGGCAGCUCCCAAUGUUGCCAACAAUACUGGGCCACAUGCUGCCAGUUGCUUUGGGGCCAAGAAGGGCAAAGAUGAGUGGUUCUCCAGAGGGAAAAAACCUAUAGAGGAUCCAGCAAACGAUACAGUGGAUUUCCCUAAAAGAACGAGUCCAGCUCGAGGCUAUGAGCUCUUAUUUCAGCCAGAGGUGGUUCGGAUAUACAUCUCACUUCUUAAGGAGAGCAAGACUCCUGCCAUCCUAGAAGCCUCAGCUGGAGCUAUCCAGAACUUGUGUGCUGGGCGCUGGACGUAUGGUCGAUACAUCCGCUCUGCUCUGCGUCAAGAGAAGGCUCUUUCUGCCAUAGCUGACCUCCUGACUAAUGAACAUGAACGGGUGGUGAAAGCUGCAUCUGGAGCACUGAGAAACCUGGCUGUGGAUGCUCGCAACAAAGAAUUAAUUGGUAAACAUGCUAUUCCUAACUUGGUAAAGAAUCUGCCAGGAGGACAGCAGAACUCCUCUUGGAAUUUCUCUGAGGACACUGUCAUCUCUAUUUUGAACACUAUCAACGAGGUUAUCGCUGAGAACUUGGAGGCUGCCAAAAAGCUUCGAGAGACACAGGGUAUUGAGAAGCUGGUGUUGAUCAACAAAUCAGGGAACCGCUCAGAAAAAGAAGUUCGAGCAGCAGCACUUGUAUUACAGACAAUCUGGGGAUAUAAGGAACUGCGGAAGCCACUGGAAAAAGAAGGAUGGAAGAAAUCAGACUUUCAGGUGAAUCUAAACAAUGCUUCCCGAAGCCAGAGCAGUCAUUCAUAUGAUGAUAGUACUCUCCCUCUCAUUGACCGGAACCAAAAAUCAGAUAAGAAACCUGAUCGGGAAGAAAUUCAGAUGAGCAAUAUGGGAUCAAACACAAAAUCACUAGAUAACAACUAUUCCACACCAAAUGAGAGAGGAGACCACAAUAGAACACUGGAUCGAUCGGGGGAUCUAGGCGACAUGGAGCCAUUGAAGGGAACAACACCCUUGAUGCAGGACGAGGGGCAGGAAUCUCUGGAGGAAGAGUUGGAUGUGUUGGUUUUGGAUGAUGAGGGGGGCCAAGUGUCUUACCCCUCCAUGCAGAAGAUUUAGCACCACUAUCUCCGUUCCAUCUGGGCUUAUAUGUACUUUUAUUUUUUGGUGGUGAAAUUGACUGAUGAUUUUCCUUUUUCUUCGCUGGACUAUUGUGCCAACUGCCAGGCUGCCUCCUGCCCUUACAGCCCUAAGUGGCUGCCUUCUUUCCAUCAACUCCCAACUUCUUCCUGUGAAGUUUAAUUGUCUCAACGCCUCCCCCUCCCCCAUUCCCUCCAUUUUUCUCCCAAGAAACCUGACUCAAUUAUUUGCAUAUUUUGAGAAACUGCUGCAGAUUAGUUCUUUUUGCCAGUUUUCCCUGGAACUCCUGGCCUUUUGUGGAGGGGAGGGAUGGAGAGAAUAGGAAUCUUCACUAGAAGCCGUGGGAAGAAUUGGAAGUUACAUGCUGUAUAUGCAAUGUCCAGCAGUCUGAUAAACUGACGAUUCUUAAUCAAGAUUUUUUUCCUGAUGGGGAAGGGACUUUUAUUUUCUUUUAGAGAGGGGAAAGUGUGAGCUCUUCCCUUAUUCCUAAUGGCUAUUUUUGAAGCAAAGAAGGCCAGCAACAUUGGCACAUGCCACCUGGCAAAGGACCCUUGAGUAAGUGAAGGUCUCCUAAAACUGGGAUUAAGAAACCUUGCUCUCCUCAUCUCCAAGGCAGGGACCAUCAAGAACCUACAGACUCCAUCUCUUCUGCAAGCCUCAUGCCAACCCUGGGCUAUUGCUGCUGCCCCUUAAACACAGGCUGUCCUUAACCCACCUCUCCUGCCCUGUGAUAUGUCUGCUGAGUUGGCCUGGCCAUUUCCAAGAGGCUGUAGAAAGGGGAGAAUGUCAAGGAAGACUUUUGGUAGAGAAGGAGCAGAAAGAUGUGUUUUUGGGAAGAAGAAGACCUCUAGGAGGAGCUAGUAGGAAUGUACAUGAAGCAAUUAGUCUGAAACUGGCUUCCCCACUCCCCCGUUUCUCCUUUUCCUAUCCUUAUAGGCCUGUCCCUUGCCUCUGCCCUGGAUUGGUUGGCAAACUAAAGGACUUGAUGUACAUAACUCCUGUCCCUUUUCCCUUACAAGGUGGGGAUUGCCCCUGGCUUUGCCUCUUCUUUGUGCCUUUGGCCUGGGGUGCAUCUCCUCCCGCCCUUCCAUGUGCCUUUCUUUGCCUCUGCAGUCUCAUUUCUCAUAAUUUUGCAAAUUAUAUUUUGUUGCUUUCUUACCUACUAUUGGCCCUAAAUAGCAGAAAGAAGAGAAGUGACCGAGAGAACCUCAGAUUCUUCAUUGAGGAUUGGUAUAGCCAUGAUUUCAGUCAUAGCAAGCUUUUGCUCAACAGCAUAUGGGUGGGAUUUUGCAAAAAUCCUAUUCUGAUGAAUCUCAAAGUAAGGCUGGUAAGAGAAGUGAGUGGUGUGACUCUUACUCCUUAGGUGCCCAGAAUUUACCAUCAUCUCUGAAGGAGUUACAGGGAAGUGGUCUCCCCAAUUCUCCCCUCCCUCCAGUAUUGCCCCCUCUCACUUUAGCAUAUAUUAAUUAGCAGGUUGGGCUAGAGAAAUCAGCUGCUAUGCGGGUUGAUUAUUAUUAUUAUUUCUAAUCCUUUUCCUUAUUUGCCUUCUACUCCCCUUAAUCUAAUCUAAAAGCUCUGUUCCAUGCAACUGGAGUUCCUUAUCCCUCUCUUCCCCUUCCCUUAUAUAUUGAGGCUAUGGGGUAGGAGAAAAGUGCACAACCCACCACCCCCUUUACUCGUGCAUUAAAAUUUCUUAUUUACCCUUUUCCCCCUUCCCAUUUCUUCCCACUUUCAUCUACCUUUUCUGGCAAAAAGGAGCCUUUUGCUCUCUGUGACCCUAAGAGCACACUGCACAGGGAAAAUUGCCCCAUCCAGACCUGGCUCCACUCUUGAUCUCUCUUGUCCUCUUCUGCUCUUUUCCUGGUGCUCUUUUUUCUCGGUGGGGUGUGGGUAAUAGAACAGCCGUGGGCUUUUGGGGACCUUUAACUUUUUUUUCUCUCUUUUGUUUAUAAAAAACACUAAACAUUCAAUUCCAGAGAACCAAAAAUCCCACCUUCCCACCGAACACUACUAAGGGGCUUGUGUUCUGCUCCAUACCUUUUCUCUUUUCUUUCUGUCUUGUUAAUGCUUUUAAAAACAAAUGAGUUUUUUAUAUAAAUAAAGUUUUUAAAGUGUGUAUGUGGGGGGUCUGUGUCAUUUCUUCACUUCAAGCUGUUAUUUCUUCCCUGCUUUGCAUCUUUGUUACUUCCUUAUGUAUCAGUGUCCUUUCCAGAGCAACCAGAAGGAGGUUAUACCAGGAUUUAUUUUGAGCUCAGCCCCAACUCUUUAUCAAGCAACAUUCUUGUUAACUAUAUGUGAAACAUUUUUUCUUCUGAAGAUUCUUAAAAAUUGAAUGUGGCUGAAGUUGAACAUGGGAGCUUAUUGCUAAUUUAGAGAUAGGAAACUGAAGCAUAAAGAAUUAAUGACUUACUUUAAUUACUGGAAUUCUUCUGCAACAUUUGACAAAACUAACCUUGAAUAAGGCCCACUGUAAUACGUAGCUCUCUUAAAUAUAACACUUAGGACUAGAAGAUUAGAAACUACCAAUCCCAACUACGUAAUAGGAAAAUGUAGGAUCAAAAGGCCCAUGUAUAUAAGUACUGACCACUGGGCCAUAAUGUUGCUUCUCAGGCUAUAUGCAGUCCUUUAGUCAGAAGUCAAUAGGCCUAUUUAUUAAUAUUUUACAGACCAUAUUACCUGGAUUACCAGGGACUAUCUUUGCUGCAGAGAUCAAGGGUUAAGAUCUAUGGGAAGAUACUUAUUUUUCUGAGGUCCUUAUGUCCUGUCAUAUAAUUAAAGACUCAAGAGAAUUUAUGUGAAAUGCUUUCUGUAUGCCCAAAUCUUUAGAUUAAAAUUAUAUAGCUGCUCCUGAUGAUGGUCCUGUCUUGUUUUAUUGAACUAGGACUUGGGUAUGAAAACUUUCAUGGGCUAGUGAGACCAGGAAAUCAACUAGCUUUUAAAGCUUGAUUUGUGUCUAACAAUUGUAGUGUUAGAUUAGAGGUUGAAGUACAAAGCCAAAAAGCUAUUAAGAGUUUACUUUCCAAAGAGUUUUGAUAGCCCUGCUUGAGAUGAUUUUUAUCUAAAUAGAAAAGCCUGGCUGCUUGUCAGCAACACUUUAUUUCCCUGUUAUGUUCUUAUCCUUUGGCAUUGAGCUAGAUACAAACCCUACUCUUCUCUCUUCCUUCUGGAUUGGUCCAUUUGUUUAUCUCAUUCAAUAAAUAUUUGCCAAGCA